GGUAGACGCGAUCUGCUGGCUACUACCGGCCUCCCCUGGCUGUUAAAAGCAGAUGGUGGCUGAGGCUGGUUCAAUGCCGGCUGCCUCCUCUGUGAAGAAGCCAUUUGGUCUCAGAAGCAAGAUGGGCAAGUGGUGCCGCCACUGCUUCCCCUGGUGCAGGGGGAGCGGCAAGAGCAACGUGGGCACUUCUGGAGACCACGAUGAUUCUGCUAUGAAGACACUCAGGAGCAAGAUGGGCAAGUGGUGCCGCCACUGCUUCCCCUGGUGCAGGGGGAGCGGCAAGAGCAACGUGGGCACUUCUGGAGACCACGACGACUCUGCUAUGAAGACACUCAGGAGCAAGAUGGGCAAGUGGUGCUGCCACUGCUUCCCCUGCUGCAGGGGGAGCGGCAAGAGCAAAGUGGGCCCCUGGGGAGACUACGACGACAGCGCUUUCAUGGAGCCGAGGUACCACGUCCGUCGAGAAGAUCUGGACAAGCUCCACAGAGCUGCCUGGUGGGGUAAAGUCCCCAGAAAGGAUCUCAUCGUCAUGCUCAAGGACACUGACAUGAACAAGAAGGACAAGCAAAAGAGGACUGCUCUACAUCUGGCCUCUGCCAAUGGAAAUUCAGAAGUAGUAAAACUCCUGCUGGACAGACGAUGUCAACUUAAUAUCCUUGACAACAAAAAGAGGACAGCUCUGACAAAGGCCGUACAAUGCCAGGAAGAUGAAUGUGCGUUAAUGUUGCUGGAACAUGGCACUGAUCCGAAUAUUCCAGAUGAGUAUGGAAAUACCGCUCUACACUAUGCUAUCUACAAUGAAGAUAAAUUAAUGGCCAAAGCACUGCUCUUAUACGGUGCUGAUAUCGAAUCAAAAAACAAGCAUGGCCUCACACCACUGUUACUUGGUGUACAUGAGCAAAAACAGCAAGUGGUGAAAUUCUUAAUCAAGAAAAAAGCAAAUUUAAAUGCACUGGAUAGAUAUGGAAGAACUGUUCUCAUACUUGCUGUAUGUUGUGGAUCGGCAAGUAUAGUCAGCCUUCUACUUGAGCAAAACAUUGAUGUAUCUUCUCAAGAUCUAUCUGGACAGACGGCCAGAGAGUAUGCUGUUUCUAGUCGUCAUAAUGUAAUUUGCCAGUUACUUUCUGACUACAAAGAAAAACAGAUACUAAAAGUCUCUUCUGAAAACAGCAAUCCAGAACAAGACUUAAAGCUGACAUCAGAGGAAGAGUCACAAAGGCUUAAAGGAAGUGAAAAUAGCCAGCCAGAGGAAAUGUCUCAAGAACCAGAAAUAAAUAAGGGUGGUGAUAGAAAGGUUGAAGAAGAAAUGAAGAAGCACGGAAGUACUCAUAUGGGAUUCCCAGAAAACCUGCCUAACGGUGCCACUGCUGACAAUGGUGAUGAUGGAUUAAUUCCACCAAGGAAAAGCAGAACACCUGAAAGCCAGCAAUUUCCUGACACUGAGAAUGAACAGUAUCACAGUGAUGAACAAAAUGAUACUCAGAAGCAACUUUCUGAAGAACAGAACACUGGAAUAUUACAAGAUGAGAUUCUGAUUCAUGAAGAAAAGCAGAUAGAAGUGGCUGAAAAUGAAUUCUGAGCUUUCUCUUAGUUAUAAGAAAGAAAAAGACCUCUUGCAUGAAAAUAGUACGUUGCAGGAAGAAAUUGUCAUGCUAAGACUGGAACUAGACGUAAUGAAACAUCAGAGCCAGCUAAGAGAAAAGAAAUAUUUGGAGGAAAUUGAAAGUGUGGAAAAAAAGAAUGAUAAUCUUUUAAAGGGUCUACAACUGAAUGAGCUCACCAUGGAUGAUGAUACUGCCGUGCUCGUCAUUGACAACGGCUCUGGCAUGUGCAAGGCCGGCUUUGCAGGUGACGAUGCCCCCCGGGCUGUCUUCCCUUCCAUCGUGGGGUGCCCCAGGCACCAGAACAUGAUGGGGGGCAUGCGUCAGAUGGAGUCCUAUGUGGGCAAUGAGGCCCAGAGCAAGAGAGGCAUCCUGACCCUGAAGUACCCCAUGGAGCACGGCAUCAUCACCAACUGGGACGACAUGGAGAAGAUCUGGCACCACACCUUCUACAAUGAGCUGCGUGUGGCUCCCGAGGAGCACCCCAUCCUGCUGACCGAGGCACCCCUGAACCCCAAGGCCAACCGUGAGAAGAUGACCCAGAUCAUGUUUGAGACCUUCAACACCCCAGCCAUGUACGUGGCCAUCCAAGCCGUGCUGUCCUUGUACACCUCUGGCCGUACUACUGGCAUUGUGAUGGACUCUGGUGACGGGGUCACCCACACUGUGCCCAUCUAUGAGGGGAAUGCCCUCCCCCAUGCCACCCUGCGCCUAGACCUGGCUGGCCGGGAACUGACUGACUACCUCAUGAAGAUCCUCACCGAGCGUGGCUAUAGUUUCACCACCAUGGCCGAGCAGGAAAUCGUGCGUGACAUCACAGAGAAGCUGUGCUAUGUUGCCCUGGACUUCGAGCAGGAGAUGGCCACAGCGGCCUCCAGCUCCUCCCUAGAGAACAGCUAUGAGCUGCCCAACGGCCAGGUCAUCACCAUUAGCAACGAGCGGUUCCGCUGCCCCGAGGUGCUCUUCCAGCCUUGCUUCCUGGGCAUGGAAUCCUGUGGCAUCCACGAAACUACCUUCAACUCUAUCAUGAAGUCUGAUGUGGACAUCCACAAAGACCUGUACACCAACACAGUGCUAUCUGGUGGCACCACCAUGUACCCUGGCAUUGCCCACAGGAUGCAGAAGGAGAUCGCUGCCCUGGCGCCUAGCACGAUGAAGAUCAAGAUUGUUGCUCCUCCCAAGCGCAAGUACUCCGUGUGGGUCGGUGGCUCCAUCCUGGCCUCGCUGUCCACCUUCCAGCAGAUGUGGAUCAGCAAGCAGGAGUAUGAUGAGUCAGGCCCCUCCAUUGUCCACCGCAAAUGCUUCUAGGUGGACGCUGACUUAGUUGCAUUACACCCUUUCUUGACAAAACCAAACUUCGCAGAAAGCCACAUGAGAUUGGUAUGGCUUUAAUUGUUUUCUUAUUUCAUUUUUUGUUUUGUUUUUUAUUGGCUUGACUCAGGAUUUAAAAACUGGAAUGGUGAAGGCGAGAGCAGUUGGUUGGAGUGAGCUUCCCCCAAAGUUCUACAAUGUGGCUGAGGACUUUGAUCGUACAUUGUUUUUCUUUUCAAUAGUCAUUCCAAAUAUUGUGAGAUGCAUUGUUUCAGGAAGCCCCUUGCCCUUCUAAAAGCCACCCCACUUCUCUCUAAGGAGAAUGGCCCAGUCCUCUCCCUAAUUCACACAGGGGAGGUGAUGGCAUUGCUUUCAUGCAAAUUACGUAAUGCAGAAUUUUUUGAAUCUUUGCCUAAAUACUUUUUAAUUUUGUUUUAUUUAGAAUGAUCAGCCUUCGCGGCCCCCCUUUUUUGUACCCCAACUUGGGGUGUAUGAAGGCUUUUGGUCUCCCUGAGAGUGGCUGGAGGCAGCCAGGGCUUACCUGUACUCUGACUUAAGGAGAGUUGGAAAAAAGUGCACACCUUAAAAAAAAUUCAAUGAGGAAGCAUUAACAAAAACAGUAUUUCUGUACAGUGGACAGCUUAGCAUGUUGACAACUGAGAAUAAAAUGCUCAGUUCUGAACUGGACAAUGUAAGACACAACGACGAAACACUGGAAAUGGAAAUUCAAUUACAUCAUUGUAGACUGGCUACUGCUCUACAUGAUUGUGACCAAAGUCAGAGAGCUGAAAGAGACUUCUUUCCAGAGAACAAGACAUGAACAGGUUUAUUUACAGAAGACAAUGAAUUCUCAUUUGUCUAACCUAAAAGAUUACAGAAUCUUUCUCAACAAGUCUAAUGUAGACAGUAAAAUCAACAGGCUAAAAAUUAAGUUCCAUGAAACAAGAUAAAACUCUGAGAGAAAAGAUGGGGCAGGCCGCCAUCUUUCCCGUUCGGGCAACUUAGUCAUUCCAGCCUGAGGGCUUUGGAGAGUACAAACUGACCAGGGAAAGAAGAGAUCCCAGAGCACAGCAUAGCUGCUUUACCAAAUCAUGGCCAGACUGCUUCUGUAAGCAGGCCCCUGAUCCUGUUCCACCUCACUGGACAGGACCUCCCAACUGGGGCCUCCAGCUACCCCCACCAGCAUCCCUUGGCCAAUGGAAAUUUGAAAUGUUCCUGGGACAGAGCUCCUGGAGAGAGGGGCAGGCCACCACCUUUGCUGUUUGGGUGACUAGCCGUUCUGGCCUGCAGGCUUUGGAGAGCCCAAGCUGACAAGGGGUAGAAGAGGUGCCUCAGCACAGCACAGCCACGCUACGAAAACAUGGCCAGACUCUUGUUUAAGUCAGUCCCCGAACACAUUUCUAGUCAGUGGGUGAAGUCUUUCAACCAGGGUCUCUGGCUACCUUGACUGCUGUUCUCUGGCCGACAGAGGUCUCAGGCCUCCCUGAGUCAGAGCUCCCGGGGGGAGGACCAGAUUGUCAUCUUUGCUGUUUGGGUGACCCAGCCAUUUCAGCCUUAGGGCUUCAGAGUGUCUGAGGUAGCCAGGGGCUGAAGUGAACCCCCAGCACAGCACAGCUGCUCUAUAAAAACGUGGCCAGACUUUUUCUUUAAGCAAGUCCCUGUUCUUAUUCCUCCUGACUAGGUAAGACUUCUCAACUUGCCUCCAGCCACAUCUUAUUGGUGUGUUCAGAUUGGCAACAGGUUCGUACCUCAGUGGUACAGAGCUCCCAGAGGAAGGGGUAGGCUAUCAUCUUCCCUGGAAAAUACGAGUCAAUUAGGGACUUGAGGGGACCCCCAGCAUUCCACAGCAGCCCUUCAGAAAAGUGGCCAGACUCUGUACUUGAUGGGCAGAUCCUCCUGGCCUGUGUCUCUAGCCAGCCCACCACUGGAGCUAUCAAGCCAGUAGCAACUCAGCAGUUCCUUGGACAGAGCUUCCAGGAGCAAAUGAAAUCCUUUCUGCCACUGCCUUUGCAGUGAACUGCCCUUGCUAUCCUCAGAAGAUAUAUCACGGGAGCAAAGACCCUAAGUGCCAUAUCAACACCUCCAAUAAGCUGCAGUUGACCCAAAGAACAAGCCAAUCCAUCUCCCAUAGGUACCACACACACUCCACUACUCAUCACCAGACAGGGAACCCUGGCUUGGGCCCACAGCACAGACCCUCCAUCCUGGGCCGAUUACACUGAGUGAUUGCUAACUCACAUGUCUCUGGGAUGGAGCACCCAGGAGACAAGCAAAGUGGUGGAGCAGCAAGUCAGGUGAUGUGGAGCCCAGAGGGCAGGGACAGCUAUCUCUCUAGGCUCCACUUGCCCUUGUGAGACACUUUGUCCCAGCACUUUAGGAAUGCUGAGGUCAGACCAGCCACAUCUCAUGUGCAAGAUUGCCCAGCAGACAUCAGGUCUGAGAGUUCCCCUUUUAAAAAAGGGGACUUGCUUAAAAAAGAAGUCUAGCCACGAUUGUGUAGAGCAGCUGUGCUGUGCUGGAGAUUCACUUUUGAGAGAGUUCUCCUCUGAGACCUGAUCUUUAGAGGCUGGGCAGUCUUGCACAUGAGAUGGGGCUGGUCUGAUCUCAGCACUCCUUAGUCUGCUUGCCUCUCCCAGGGCCCCAGCCUGGCCACACCUGCUUACAGGGCACUCUCAGAUGCCCAUACCAUAGUUUCUGUGCUAGUGGACCGUACCAUAUCAGUGGAGAGCUGCAGCAAGGUGGCCCCUACGGCCACGCACCAGCCUGCACAUUACCUCUCCAUACUGCAGCCCUUUAUAUGGAAACUUCCUACAUCACUUUGCUGUGUGUGUUUACACAGGUGGAUUUUGCUUUACUUGCACUGACAGCACACAGGAGGGCAGCACACACCCCAACCCACAUCAACUGCCAUUAAAGAAAAGAAAUUUCAGCCCAUAAUUUCAUGUCCAGCAAAAUUAGGCAUCAUAAGUGAAGGAGAAAUAAGAUCCUUUUCAGACAAGCAAAUGCUGAGGGAAUUCAAUAUCACCAGAUCUACCUUACAAGAGCUCCUGAAGGAAGCACUAAAUAUGGAAAGAAAAAACCAUCACCAGCCACUACAAAAAUGCAGUGAAGAACGCAGUGAAUUACGCAGUCCAGUGAUGCUAAAAACCAACCACAUACGUUAAGUCUGCAAAAUAACCAGCUGACAGCAUGACGACAGGAUAAAAUCCACACAUACCAUUACUAACCUUAAAUGAAAAUGGGCUAAAUGCUCCCAUUGAAAGACACGGGGCAAGCUGGAUAAAGAACCAAGACCCACUGGAGUAUGCUGUCUUCAAGAAACCCAUCUCACAUGCGGUGGCAUACAUAGGCUCAAAAUAAAGGAAUGGAGAAAAAUAUUUCAAGCAAAUGGAAAACAGAAAAAAGCAGGUGUUGCACUCCUACUUUCUGACAAAACAGACUAUGCGAAUAAAGAUAAAAAAGAGAAGGACAUUACAAAGGUGGUCCUGACCUUUGAUAAAUCUCAUUGCUUGAUACCAACCUGGGCUGUUUUAAUUGCCCAAACCAAUAGGAUAAUUUGCUGAGGUUGUGGAGCUUCUCCCCUGCAGAGAGUCCCUGAUCUCCCAAAAUUUGGUUGAGAUGUAAGGUUGAUUUUGCUGUACAACUCCUUUUCUGAAGUUUUACUCAUUUCCAAAAAGGAAGGCAAGUUUUCCUGCUUCCAUGACGAUGGAGAGCAGGCAUCUCCUUUCCUGAGUUUCAGCUUGCUUCUGACAGG